GUUCCCAGGGUGGCGCCUGCUCUCCAUCCAGGCCCCAUUCCGGCUCCCACCCGACGCUGCUUUUGUUCCCACGUUUCGGGGGGCAGCUGGCACUGUGAUUCCUGCCCCAUGAGUGCCUAGAGGCACGGAGCCACCAGGGAUCACCCCACGUGGGACACAGGGCUUGGGGAGGAUGGGGCAGGACCAGACCAAGCAGCAGAUCGAGAAGGGGCUCCAGCUGUACCAGUCCAACCAGACAGAGAAGGCAUUGCAGGUGUGGACAAAGGUGCUGGAGAAGAGCUCGGACCUCAUGGGGCGCUUCCGCGUGCUGGGCUGCCUGGUCACAGCCCACUCGGAGAUGGGCCGCUACAAGGAGAUGCUGAAGUUCGCUGUGGUCCAGAUCGACACGGCCCGGGAGCUGGAGGAUGCCGACUUCCUCCUGGAGAGCUACCUGAACCUGGCACGCAGCAACGAGAAGCUGUGCGAGUUUCACAAGACCAUCUCCUACUGCAAGACCUGCCUUGGGCUGCCUGGUACCAGGGCAGGUGCCCAGCUCGGAGGCCAGGUCAGCCUGAGCAUGGGCAAUGCCUUCCUGGGCCUCAGCGUCUUCCAGAAGGCCCUGGAGAGCUUCGAGAAGGCCCUGCGCUAUGCCCACAACAAUGAUGACGCCAUGCUCGAGUGCCGCGUGUGCUGCAGCCUGGGCAGCUUCUAUGCCCAGGUCAAGGACUACGAGAAAGCCCUGUUCUUCCCCUGCAAGGCGGCAGAGCUUGUCAACAACUAUGGCAAAGGCUGGAGCCUGAAGUACCGGGCCAUGAGCCAGUACCACAUGGCCGUGGCCUAUCGCCUGCUGGGCCGCCUGGGCAGUGCCAUGGAGUGUUGUGAGGAGUCUAUGAAGAUCGCGCUGCAGCACGGGGACCGGCCACUGCAGGCGCUCUGCCUGCUCUGCUUCGCUGACAUCCACCGGAGCCGUGGGGACCUGGAGACAGCCUUCCCCAGGUACGACUCCGCCAUGAGCAUCAUGACCGAGAUCGGAAACCGCCUGGGGCAGGUGCAGGCGCUGCUGGGUGUGGCCAAGUGCUGGGUGGCCAGGAAGGCGCUGGACAAGGCCUGCCCCCCUACCCUGUGCUUCCCUGUGAGCAAGGCCUGUCAGACAGCUCUGCCCGCAGCCCUGGCCUAUGCUCACCUUCCAGGCUCUGGAUGCCAUCGAGAGAGCCCAGGAUCUGGCCGAGGAGGUGGGGAACAAGCUGAGCCAGCUCAAGCUGCACUGUCUGAGCGAGAGCAUUUACCGCAGCAAAGGGCUGCAGCGGGAACUGCGGGCGCACGUUGUGAGGUUCCACGAGUGCGUGGAGGAGACGGAGCUCUACUGCGGCCUGUGCGGCGAGUCCAUAGGCGAGAAGAACAGCCGGCUGCAGGCCCUACCUUGCUCCCACAUCUUCCACCUCAGGUGCCUGCAGAACAACGGGACCCGGAGCUGUCCCAACUGCCGCCGCUCAUCCAUGAAGCCUGGCUUUGUAUGACUCCUGGCAGCAGGCGUGGGCUUCCUCCUCGCCACUCCUGCUCUUUCUCCACUGCACGCCAGAGGCCCAUUUACUCCUGGGGCAGCUGCCAGGUCGUCCUCACCAUAGCCAAGGCCUUGGGGCCUGCCCAGGGCUGCUCCCCUGGGCCCAGCUCCCCUCCCUGCCUCUUUGUACUUUGCUCUUUAUAGAAAAAUAAACUGUUUGUACCUGG